CUACAGGCGCCCGCUGCCAAACUCCUGACCUCAGGUGAUCCAUCUGCCUCAGCUUCCCAAAGUGCUGGGAUUACAGGCGUGAGCCACCGCACCCGGCCGUUGAACGUUGAUCACCCGAGAGACUUGGCUUCUCUUCAGCCUUAGCUGUGCAACCUGGGGUCCAGCUCAAAUCGUUGGAAUGUGGAAGUCCUUCCUCUCGCCCCGUCCUGAGGAGCAGCUGCAGGAGCUUCAUGAGUGUUUUCACUGGAACUUGUGGAGGAGUUUCCUUUGAUCCCUCAUGGAGAGACGGAAGCAUGAGGGAGCCCUCAACAUUUAUUCUGAAGAUGAAGAGAGUCCUGCAGCUUUUUGGAGUUUGUGAAGUCAGCCCGGCCCUGUACAGAUGUGGAAACCGAGGCCCAGGAAGUUUGUGAGCCAGCCCGGCCCUGUACAGGUGUGGAAACCGAGGCCCAGGAAGUUUGUGAGCCAGCCCGGCCCUGUACAGAUGUGGAAACCGAGGCCCAGGAAGUUUGUGAGCCAGCCUGGCCCUGUACAGAUGUGGAAACCGAGGCGUAGGAAGGAAGCCCUUCUCUGACCUCAGAGCUGAAAUGGCCAGUGCUGGGUGGGCAUUGAGGGGUCACACAGAAAAGAAUGUUUCAGGCCAUGUUCAGGGGAUACUUCCUGCAGGGCCCUUGGAAAGUUCCGGAGCGCUUACAUUGUCCAUGUGUGAGUGUCUCCUCUUUCUUGCCUGUGUGGGGUUUUCUCAAAUGCUUUGAGUUGGCCAAACCACAGUUGUGCGCCACUUAACAGUGCGGAUACAUUCUGAGAAAAACCUCGUUAGGUGAUGUCGUCUUGCAAACAUUAAAGAGUGCAUUUACACAAGGCUGGCAGGCACGGCCUCCUGCACCCCCAGGCUGUGUGCCCGGGUGCCAGAGCCUGGGGCUCCUGGGCUGCAGACCUGCACAGCCUGUCACAGCAUUUAAUCACAUCCAAACACGGAAAAGGCAAAAACGUAAAGAUGCAGUGUUACAAUCCUAGGGGACUCCUGUCACCUGUGUGGUCUGUUCUUGACUAUUGUGAGUCACUGACUUUUCCCCCUGGGAAACUACCUUAACUUGUCUUCAACUGAAAUUUUUUCAGCCUGCAAAGAUGAGUUGUGCCUCAGAGGUUGCUCGUGUUCUGAGGUGCCUCUUCACCACUGCCUGUCAGGCUGCUAACCAGAGUGCCCCAGACCACAGCAGAAGCGACAGCAGCCAAGGAUCGGGGGAGCCCACCCUGCUCCUGGGUAUCUUUACGGCAGGCAGCAGAGUAACAGCCUCAGACUUACCUCUUCAGCCAGAGACCCCUCAGCCCAGGAGGAGUGAGGCCGGGCCAGCAGCGGGGGCCCGGGAAGCCCCAUGUCUUGGGACCUGCUGGGGCAGGGCCCCCUGGAUGUCAGGCUGCAGGUCCGGCAGCUGGGGAGGGGAUGAGGGCCUCCCACCAGCUCUGCCCAUCAGCCAGAUCCCUGGGAGAGGCAGCACUUGCUGGCCACAGAGUCGGCCCCAGUCUCACCUGGCUCCCCUCCCCCACCAGCUGGGCCCUGCACUGCCCCAGCCCACGCGGCGCCUCACCCCUCCUUGACAGAACAGUAUCUCUGGGACGGACAAGUUAAUCCAAGACCCACAGUAGCCCUGGAUCCCCUGGGAGAGGUGGCUGCCCAGCUCCAGGGCCAGCUUGGAGGAGCCAACUUCAAAAGCCUCCGCCUGGCCUGCCCCUCUGCAGUCCUCCAGGCAGCCUGUCCAGGGAAGCGGUUGGCUGGUGUUGGACCUGGUGCGGCAGUGCACACCCUGCCCAAGGACCCCAGGAUCAUGUGCGUGGCCUGCUGGCGGGAGUGAGGGAGGGCAAGACCCUGAAAGGCCCAUGGUACCCCCUAAGCCUGCACUCUGGGCGCUCCUGCUGGCGCUGCUGGGGACCGCGCCAAGCCGCGCCUAUUCCCCGGCCUGCAGCGUCCCCGACGUGCUCCGCCACUAUCGCGCCAUCAUCUUCGAGGAUCUGCAGGCCGCCGUGAAGUGGGGCGGGGCGGGGGCCGAAAAGACCAGGCCAGGCUCCAGACACUUUCAUUUCAUACAGAAAAACCUGACUAGACCCGGGAGCUCGGGACGGCGGGGACGGCCUCGGGCCUCCUGUGGCGCCCAGAAGGAGCACAGUAUCCUCCUGUCCAUCUCGUCCCUGGGUCGGACCCUGCGCGGGGCGGUGGCCGGGGGCCGCCGCGGGGCCCUGGAGAGAGCUGCUUGGACCGUGGCUGUGCGCACCGAGGCGGUGAUGCGGCGCCACUGCAGGACGCUGCGCCAGCGGAGCCGGCGGCCCAAGAUGCGCCCUGCCCGGCGUCGCGGCGGCCGAAGGCAGCUCCUGCUGCGCGCCCUGGACGCCGUCGCCACCUGCUGGGAGAAGCUCUUCGCGCUGCGCGCCCCGGCCUCCAGGGACUCCUAGCGCGGCCCGUCCUGGCCCUGCGCGGGGAGGAGAACCAGCGGGGCCGCGGCAGAGCCUGGAGACGCGCCUCGUUCUGUAGACUUGUUGGUGACCUCGGCCCCUCGCUCGACGCAGCCCGCGCUCCCCGGAGGGCCCAGGACUUGGAGAAGGGAGCGCGCCUGGCCGCCGCUGGGUCACGGAGGAGGCCCGCCCUCCACGCGCCGAAGGCCUCAAUAAACGGAGCUGGCGCUGCGGGUCCGGCA